GCAGUUCAGACCCCCCCACACCCAUCAAAGAGCCGCUCCUCCCCCCCGCAGGCGCCUUCGCCGCCUCCCUCCCUUCCUUUCCUUUCCGCUCCUCUUCCGACCUGUCCACCCGGGAGGAAGGGAGCUGGAAAGGGGGCGGAAACCUCUCCCCUCCAAAAAGCACAACAAAACUGUUCAGUGCGGAGGAGCCGGGUUCGCCCCUGCCGGACAGCGGGGGGCUUUGUUCCCCGCAGUUGUUUCCUGCCCAUUUGACCUGUCAGCUGCUGGGGAAACGCUGCUGUUGACCUUUGGUUGAACUGCUAAGGCGAUUUUGCUGAUUUUUCUUUCUUUUUCCGCGAGGGCUGUCUUUUGCUCCUCCAAAUGAGCCCAGUCCCCCUCCCUUCUCCCCAAAGCGCUCCAAGAGAAAGUGCCAGGAAGGGGCUUGUCCCGGAAGGCCUGGCGGCUGAGCGGGGCCAGGUCCUGGUUAGGCCACCAGGGUGGGCGUCCGCGCCAUUGUUUGAGCUUGUCGGCGCUGGUGGGAGAGAUGAGGGCAAUUCCUCUGGGACGCAAGUCCCCUCGAAUGGCCGGGGCUGGCCGGGAUGUUCCCCGCACGGCGCUGCCCUCGAGUCCCCCCGAUGGAGAGCGCGGGCGCGCCUUCCUUCGCUGGCGUCCAAACCCGGGACCAGCUAGAACACAGCAGGGCUGGGACUGGGUUCCAGCCCCACGUGGAGUCUGGAUUUGUUUUGUUGUGUUUUGCUUUCCUUCCUGGAAGAAAUCCCGAGGGGACCGCCCUAGAGCGGCAGCUCCAGGACCUCGGCCCUUGGGCUUCCGGGGGUGCAGCCACUUAGGCCCCGCUCCCGGGGAGAGAGGGAUUAUUUUUUAAGAUUUAUCCCCAGGGCGCGCGGCAUUUCCCUGUCCCUCGUGAAUCCCGUUGAGAGUCCUCCCUCCCCAACCUCCUCCAUUUCCCCAGCCAGACCGAUUCGAGAGCCCUGGAGAUUCUGGGCGAGGCUAGUGACUGGGUAGUACAGGCCUCUAGCCCCACCAUUGCUCUCUCUGUCUUCAGUUCCCCAGGAGGGCAAUGGCAUCAAACAGCACAGCUCUGGGGGAUGUCAAUAUUGCAUACCUUUUCUACCUAAAGGGAAAAUGACUCGCUUUUCUGCUUGCAAAUAUGGUAGUUUCUGCUUACAAAUGUAAUACAAUGCCCAUGACAGCCAAGGACUGGAAGCAUAAGUUGCUAGGUCUUACAGGUGAUUUUUUACAAUGAAGCAAACUCACUAUGUUAGACACCAUUUACAUUGGAUGUCUCCAACUAACAAAAGUAACUAAAGACAGAUGUAGGUGUAAAUUGAGAGUGAAAUUUGACCCUUUAGACCGUCACAACUUCCUUGGGCUUAUCCUGGGUGCUUAUAGGAGAGGUGGGCUCCACCCACAAAAAUGGACUGCUCAGAAAAAUGAGGGAGAGAGAAAGGGUGGCCACUUUCCCGAGCCAAGAAAUUCCUUGAAAAAAAAUCAGAACAUCUGAAACCAGAGAGCCGAUUUCCUUACCGGGAGGCAGUUCCUGGCUAACGAAGAGGAAGCACGAUGGGAAGAAAAGUUCACUCCAACGGAAGCCAGUUUGCUGAACAUAGCAGAUCGCCCAGGAGGACUGGGAGAGACUGCAAACCAGUUCGAGCCCCCAGCAUGGCGUUAGGUGUCAGCCAGCUGGCAGGAAGGUCCAGGUGUCUGUGUUCAGAGUCUCAAGGCGGCUAUGAGAGGUUUUCCUCCGAGUACCCAGAAUUCUGUUCUAAAACCAAGGCCCUGGCAGCCAUCCCACCCCCGGUUCCCCCCAGUGCCACAGAGCCCUUGGACCUGGGCUGCAGCUCCUGUGGGACCCCACUACACGACCAGGGGGGUCCUGUGGAGAUCCUUCCCUUCCUCUACCUCGGCAGUGCCUACCAUGCUGCCCGGAGAGACAUGCUGGACGCCCUGGGCAUCACGGCUCUGUUGAAUGUCUCCUCGGACUGCCCAAACCACUUUGAAGGACACUAUCAGUACAAGUGCAUCCCAGUGGAAGAUAACCACAAGGCCGACAUCAGCUCCUGGUUCAUGGAAGCCAUAGAGUACAUCGAUGCCGUGAAGGACUGCCGUGGGCGCGUGCUGGUGCACUGCCAGGCGGGCAUCUCGCGGUCGGCCACCAUCUGCCUGGCCUACCUGAUGAUGAAGAAACGGGUGAGGCUGGAGGAGGCCUUCGAGUUCGUUAAGCAGCGCCGCAGCAUCAUCUCGCCCAACUUCAGCUUCAUGGGGCAGCUGCUGCAGUUCGAGUCCCAGGUGCUGGCCACGUCCUGUGCUGCGGAGGCUGCUAGCCCCUCGGGACCCCUGCGGGAGCGGGGCAAGACCCCCGCCACCCCCACCUCGCAGUUCGUCUUCAGCUUUCCGGUCUCCGUGGGCGUGCACUCGGCCCCCAGCAGCCUGCCCUACCUGCACAGCCCCAUCACCACCUCUCCCAGCUGUUAGAGCCGCCCUGGGGGCCCCAGAACCAGAGCUGGCUCCCAGCAAGGGUAGGACGGGCCGCAUGCGGGCAGAAAGUUGGGACUGAGCAGCUGGGAGCAGGCGACCGAGCUCCUUCCCCAUCAUUUCUCCUUGGCCAACGACGAGGCCAGCCAGAAUGGCAAUAAGGACUCCGAAUACAUAAUAAAAGCAAACAGAACACUCCAACUUAGAGCAAUAACGGCUGCCGCAGCAGCCAGGGAAGACCUUGGUUUGGUUUAUGUGUCAGUUUCACUUUUCCGAUAGAAAUUUCUUACCUCAUUUUUUUAAGCAGUAAGGCUUGAAGUGAUGAAACCCACAGAUCCUAGCAAAUGUGCCCAACCAGCUUUACUAAAGGGGGAGGAAGGGAGGGCAAAGGGAUGAGAAGACAAGUUUCCCAGAAGUGCCUGGUUCUGUGUACUUGUCCCUUUGUUGUCGUUGUUGUAGUUAAAGGAAUUUCAUUUUUUAAAAGAAAUCUUCGAAGGUGUGGUUUUCAUUUCUCAGUCACCAACAGAUGAAUAAUUAUGCUUAAUAAUAAAGUAUUUAUUAAGACUUUCUUCAGAGUAUGAAAGUACAAAAAGUCUAGUUACAGUGGAUUUAGAAUAUAUUUAUGUUGAUGUCAAACAGCUGAGCACCGUAGCAUGCAGAUGUCAAGGCAGUUAGGAAGUAAAUGGUGUCUUGUAGAUAUGUGCAAGGUAGCAUGAUGAGCAACUUGAGUUUGUUGCCACUGAGAAGCAGGCGGGUUGGGUGGGAGGAGGAAGAAAGGGAAGAAUUAGGUUUGAAUUGCUUUUUAAAAAAAAAAGAAAAGAAAAAGACAGCAUCUCACUAUGUUGCCAAGGCUCAUCUUGAGAAGCAGGCGGGUUGGGUGGGAGGAGGAAGAAAGGGAAGAAUUAGGUUUGAAUUGCUUUUUUAAAAAAAAAGAAAAGAAAAAAAAAGACAGCAUCUCACUAUGUUGCCAAGGCUCAUCUCAAGCUCUUGGGCUCAAGAGAUCCUCCCACCUCGGCCUCCUGAGUAGCUGGGACUGCAGGUGUGUGUCAUCAUGACCAAUGUGAAUUGCUUUUGAAGCUGGUUCAUGGGCAUGUAGGCCACCGAAGCAAUUUUAGACCACAGUAAGUCAAGCUUUUUUCCCUCCGAUGAUCACUGGGUGGUUGCAGCAUUUUUUGCAUAAACCUGCCUAAGACUUGUCUAUCGUCUGUGAUCAAUAUGCCAUAUUACACUAAGGUGCUCCUGGAAAAUUGGGUGCAGUUCAAAUUUUCCUACAGCAAAUCAUUUGGCAAGGCCAGCCAUUGGGGAAACCAGACAACUAGAGAUAACCCUGAAAUGAAUCCUUUUGUAAAUUGAAGCACCAUCUUUUCUUUUUUUGCAUAAAUUGGAGGUUUUAAUUUUAGGGCAGUUACCUGAAGUGAAAUAUACCAACAAUUUCUUGUGUUCUUUAAAUUCCUAGUUAGGUGAAUAUUUUUGAAGGUCCUCUUUUGAAUAAAGAGGGGAAUGGACACCACAUUUCAGGUCUUCUCGAAGUGUGGAAGGGCAAGAGAGCAUCAGUGAGCUGAUGGUGGAUUGCUUACAUCGGAUUCCAUUGGUAUGAAUUUCCCAAACUGGAAAUCAAAGCGCCAGGGUGGGGUUGGGGCUGACUGCUGGUGAGGGGGCUGGCCGCUGGCUCCCGUGACGUGCGUCAUGGGCACGCAGGCGCCAUUUUGAAUCUAUCGUCGGCACGUGGGUGCCAUUUUGAAUCCUUAGUUGGGCCUUUCUAAAUGGAGAAUGGCUUUGGAGGGAGACACGUUUUCUGUGGGGAGGGUUUGGGGGGGAGGGAGGAGGGAACAAGCUACAUGCUAUUUUGUUUGUAGUAUUGUGGAACAGUCUUGUUAUGGAGUGCCAGCUUAGAGGUUGUUGCAAACUUGUCUAGAAGUGAGAGCAUGGUUUUUUUUAGCCCUUUGAGAGUCUACAUCUAAUGAACAUUCUUGCUCACCCAUAAAUAACGUCAAGCCUCAAUGUCACCGUCACGUUGGGAUACUCUUUCUCAUCUGGCAUCCUAGACAGGACAAGGUUGGUUACCUUUCCUUCCAUGAACCAUGAACCUGUGACGGCAUCAUUCAUCCUGACUUCACCAAGCUCCGCCUGUGGGUGAGGCCAGAGCUCCCACUGGCAAUUUUUAGAAGAGCCAGAGGCUCCCUGCUUCCUCUAGAAAUAACAGUUCAGGGUGAAGCAUGGAGGGUUUCAGUUCCCAGACAAUGGAACCAUUUAGAGACAACACAGUUGGACAUUUCCACUUUUUCCUUGAUUCCUGGAAGUCCAGUGGGUUCUGCAGCUGAAAAAGCCCUGGGUCCCAGCAGCAGAGAGACAGGACAGAGGGGAUGCUUGGGCGGGGAGGGACGGUAACCUGCAGAACAGAUUCCAUUUUUAUAGAACGAGUACACGUUUGCUAAAACAGUCCUGCUUUCCCAGACUGGAUUCCCACCACAGGGACAGUCGGAACUCAGGACUAGCUCCAGCGACAUCUUUCCUCCGAAUUCAAGCCUUCUAUCACAAUGUCAAAACAGCUAUUUAUAAAGCCAUUUUCAUUGUACUUGAUAACAGCACGAGUCCCAAAACUUUUAGAAAUAAAAUAGGACAUUGGCUUGAUUGAAAAGAGGGACUUUUUAAAAAUUGUUCUUUCGUCAGAAGCCUUUUGGAUGACUUACAAUAGCUCUGAUGAAGAUACCACCCCAGCGUCAGUCCAAUAGGUCAGUGAGUUUCAACAGGCAUCCAUCCCUCCCAUGAAGGGAUUCUGGUGAUGGGAAGUUUCUGUAAUGACAGGAAAGCAUUGACCCUCAUUGAUUGUCAACUUUGGUAUUAGCCAUGAAAGACAGGAUGCUCAUUGGGUGUUCUGUAGAGUGAGGAAUGCUGCCUAUUCCCUCCCAGAACGUCUGACCCAGGGGUGUGUGUUGAGGAGCCCUGGGGGAAAUGGACCAAGUUUUCCCACAGAGCAGUAUUAGGCUGAAGAGCAGGUGACUGGUAGGCCCCAGCUCCCAUCAUUCCCUCCCAAAGCCAUUUUGUUCAGUUGCUCAUCCACGCUGGAUUCCAGAGAGUUUUCCAAUUUGGGAAGCCAUGAGAAAGGUUUUUAAAUCUUGGGAAGAUGGAGAGAGGGACAUAGGAUAGUUGACUCCAACAUGACAGGAAGAGGCUGGAGAUUGGGAAUUGGCCAUCAACCAAGCCUGUAGUAGUAAAGCCAUGGUCCCGCAUUGGAAUUACUUGGGGAACUUAUACAGUUCUGAUACCCAGGCUCUCCUAGACCAGUUCAACCAAUUCUAGGUGGGGGACUCAGGCAUCAGUGUGUUUCGUAGCUCCCCGGGUGUUUUCCCUGUGCAGCCGAGCUUGGGAAACUGCCAUGCUUUUUGGAUGUCAAGGCGCUGUUGGAGGCUGGGUGUGACAGCACAGAGCCAGGUUGUCUUGUGGAAACCACAGCCACGGGUUUGCCACUGGCUCAGCAUGGCCUCACUGCCAGUCCCAGCCUGGCUGAGGGACAAGAUGGUUUCUCUUGGGAGUUCCUGAGUGGAGCACCCUUCCAGGCUUUUUGAAAGCCAGCUGAUCUGUGGAGCCUUGUUAAGGGACUCAAUACGGUGUUUGGAUAUUGAUGUUUUUCCUUGAGACUGUCUUGUCCAUCAAUAAAGAUGGAGGAUGUCUCCUCUUUGAACCCCGCUUCCCCACCAGUACUCUCUCUCCCUUAGAGUUUAUGAGUUAUUCAAGGAGGAGACUUCUUAAAGACAGCAACGCAAUUCUUGUAACUUGUGUAAAUAGCCCCAUCUUUCAGAGUGAUACCAUUUCUACAUUUGAUAAUGCCUGUAUUCCUGUAGGAUGUAUAUAGUUUAGGGGAUUUUUUUUUUGUUUGGUUUUGUUUUUUAGAAGUCAAUAUGUCUGGUUUUAUUUAUUGCUUGAAAAAGAUCAUUUGAAAAAAAUAAAUACAUUUUCAACCA